AUACGCUGGUCUCCACAUCGACUGCGCCUUGUGUCCCGGGCGCUCCUGGUCUACAAUGGCAGCGGCCGCCAGCCCCGCGAUCCUUCCGCGCCUCGCGAUUCUUCCGUACCUGCUAUUCGACUGGUCCGGGACGGGGCGGGCCGACGCUCACUCUCUCUGGUAUAACUUCACCAUCAUUCAUUUGCCCAGACAUGGGCAACAGUGGUGUGAGGUCCAGAGCCAGGUGGAUCAGAAGAAUUUUCUCUCCUAUGACUGUGGCAGUGACAAGGUCUUAUCUAUGGGUCACCUAGAAGAGCAGCUGUAUGCCACAGAUGCCUGGGGAAAACAACUGGAAAUGCUGAGAGAGGUGGGGCAGAGGCUCAGACUGGAACUGGCUGACACUGAGCUGGAGGAUUUCACACCCAGUGGACCCCUCACGCUGCAGGUCAGGAUGUCUUGUGAGUGUGAAGCCGAUGGAUACAUCCGUGGAUCUUGGCAGUUCAGCUUCGAUGGACGGAAGUUCCUCCUCUUUGACUCAAACAACAGAAAGUGGACAGUGGUUCACGCUGGAGCCAGGCGGAUGAAAGAGAAGUGGGAGAAGGAUAGCGGACUGACCACCUUCUUCAAGAUGGUCUCAAUGAGAGACUGCAAGAGCUGGCUUAGGGACUUCCUGAUGCACAGGAAGAAGAGGCUGGAACCCACAGCACCACCCACCAUGGCCCCAGGCUUAGCUCAACCCAAAGCCAUAGCCACCACCCUCAGUCCCUGGAGCUUCCUCAUCAUCCUCUGCUUCAUCCUCCCUGGCAUCUGAGAAGAGUCAUUUAGAGUGACAGGUGGAAGGUGAUAUCAAGAAGCCUCUGUUAGCCUGGUCUGGUUCCUGCUCUCCCUUCAGGGAGGCCGCCUGUCUACUCACCACUGUGCCUUUCUGGAAAGCAGGAGUUCAAGCCUUAGCAAGCCCAGAGGCCCCCAGCAGAUGAUGAGGACAUUGUCGGCUCAACAUCUCAGGCCACUCAUUACCUUCGCUCAUGAUCCCAGCAGCCAUUUUUCUUUUUUUUUUUUUGUUUUUUUUUUUUUUUGAGACGGAGUCUCGCUCUGUCGCCCAGGCCGGACUGCGGACUGCAGUGGCGCAAUCUCGGCUCACUGCAAGCUCCGCUUCCCGGGUUCACGCCAUUCUCCUGCCUCAGCCUCCCGAGUAGCUGGGACUACAGGCACCCGCCACCGCGCCCGGCUAAUUUUUUGUAUUUUUAGUAGAGACAGGGUUUCACCUUGUUAGCCAGGAUGGUCUCGAUCUCCUGACCUCAUGAUCCACCUGCCUCGGCCUCCCAGAGUGCUGGGAUUACAGGCGUGAGCCACCGCGCCCGGCCAGCCAUUUUUCUUAACACCUUCUGCCACUUUCUCUCGGUGCUAAUGGAUGGAAUUCCUGCACAAGUUUUAACUGAACAAGAAAUCCCAGCAAAAGGCAUUUUCUUUCUACUUCUUUGAUUGUGGAAAAGCAGACAUUUCUCUGAAGCAUGACCUUAUUCUUCGAAACGGUAUUGCUAGUAAAAUAGCAUGCAGGACUUCAGACCUCAGGGAUCCUUUCCAUGCACUGACCAAGAAUUGUAUUAAUCCUUUUUAUCAUUAUAGUUUUUUUACAUUUUCUCAUUCUGUCAACCAUAUUGGAGUGAAGUGGCAUAGUCAUCACUCACUGUAAUCUCCAACUCCUGGGCUCAAGUGAUCCUCUAGACUCAGCCUCUAGAGUAGCUGGGACUACAGGCGCAUGCCACCAUGCCUGGCAAAUUGUUUUAUAUUUAGGUAGAGAUUGGGUCUUCCUAUGUUGCGCAGGUAAUAAAACUGUGAAAAUCCUGGAAUAUAAGCUAAGAAAUACCAAUGUGGACAUAGGGCCUGGCAAAGAUUUCAUGAAGAAGACACUAAAAACAAUUGUAACAAAAACAAAAAUUGACAAAUGGGACCUCAUUAAACUAAAGAGCUUCUGCACAGAAAAAGAAACUAGCAACACGGUAAACAGACAGCGUGUAGAAUGGGGAAACUAUUUGCAAACUCUGCAUCUGACAAAGGUCCAAUAUCCAGAAUCUACAAAGUACUUAAACAAUUAGACAAGCAAGAAAAAAAAACCCAAUUAAAAAAUGUGCAAAGACAUGAACAGACACUUUUCAAAAGAAGACAUACAAGUGGCCAACAAACGUGAAAAAAUGCUCAAUAUCACUAAUCAUCAGAUAAGUGCAAAUCAAAACUGCAAUGAGUUACCAUCUCUUACCAGUCACAAAGUUGGAGAUGGUGGUGAGGCUGCAGAGGAAAAGAAACAGACACUGUUGGUGGGAAAGCAAACUUGUUCAGCCGCUAUGGAAAGCAGUUUGGAGAUUUCUCCAAGAACUUAAAAUAGAACUACCAUUCAAGCCUGCAAUCCCACUACUCGGGAUAUAUCCACAGGAAAAGAAUUCAUUUUAUCCAAAAGACACCUGCACCAAUAUGUUCAUUACAGUGCUAUUCUUACUAGCAAGGACACAGAAUCAACCUAAGUGCCCAGCAACACUGAAUUGAAUGAAAAAAAUGUGGUACAUAAACACCAUGGAAAUCUAUGCAGCCACCAAACACAGCAAAAUCAUGUCCUUUUCAGCAACAUGGAUGGAACUAGAGGCUAUUAUCCUAAGCAACCUAAUGCAAGAACAGAAAACUACAUACUGCAUGUUCCCAUUGGAAAGUGGCAGCUACACAUUGAAUUCACAUGAACCAGAGGCACUGGAGAUUACUAGACAGGUGAGACAGGAGGGGCACCUGGGCUGAAAAACCACCUGUUGGGUACCAUGCUUACUGUUUGAGUGAUGAGAUCAUUGGGACACCAAGCCUCAGCCUUCCAAAAUCUACCCAUGUAACAAACCUGUAUGUGUACCCUUUAAUCUAUAAUAAAGGUUAAAAUUAAAGAUUCGUAAGUAAAAUAAAAUGACAUAGAGCCCUCCAAAAAAUGGGGUUAACUGAGUGGAACGAGAGAACUUUGCACUAUGAACGCUAACCCAGAUCAAAAACUAAACUCUAGUCAUUUAAAAUAAUCGUAAGUUGUAUAUGAUGAUAAUUGUAUAAAAGUUAUACGUGAAAGUGCCAAACCCUAAAAUUAAACACUGCAUAAUGAAAUUA